AGUGUGCAGUAAGAGAUAACCUGGCAAGUGGUAGUGGCGCUUCUCGGGUGCUGUGCUUCACGUUUUGGUACUAAAGGCCGAGACUGUUGUGGCGACGGCGACCUCUACGGCAACGGCUUAAGCUCUCGGAGGAGUGGCAGAGUACGAUCUGAAGGAGGGGCUUCUGGUUAGCCCAGGUUCCAUCAUAAUGAAUGGAUCCAAUAUGGCAAAUACAUCACCGAGUGUAAAAUCCAAAGAGGACCAGGGGUUAAGUGGGCACGAUGAAAAGGAAAACCCAUUUGCAGAGUACAUGUGGAUGGAGAAUGAAGAGGAUUUCAACAGACAGGUGGAGGAGGAACUGCAGGAGCAAGACUUCUUGGACCGCUGCUUCCAAGAGAUGCUGGAUGAAGAAGACCAAGACUGGUUUAUUCCCUCACGAGACCUGCCUCAGGCCAUGGGACAGUUGCAACAGCAGUUAAAUGGACUGUCAGUCAGUGAAGGUCAUGAUUCUGAAGAUAUUUUGAGCAAAAGUAACCUGAACCCAGAUGCCAAGGAGUUUAUUCCAGGAGAGAAGUACUGAGCCGAGAAAGCUUUGAGGAAGACUUGUCUGUCCCCACAUCUGGGGAUAGUAAUGCACAAAAUGGUGGAGCUGAAGAGGGGGAUGGGGCGGGCGAGGGGUGCACAGCGGGAAGGGGAGUGGUGGUCUCACAAUACUGUGACUCUGAGUAACUAAUAUGCUCAGUCUUAUUCUAAGCCUCUGAGUAUUUCUAUUUUGUUCUGCUGACUUUUGUUUGGGGAGUUUCCUGUUUUGUUUUUUUAAAUAGCUCUUUCGAGUUAAGGAAAUUGCAUUUUCCCCCCUUCAUCAGAAGUGUUCCGCGGUGUGUAUUUAAACAAAAUAAGCUGACUAAGAAAAACUGGAUAUUUAGGAAAUGCCCCUCUCACCCUGCUGUAUACUUAUCAGGGACAGUGAGCACCUGGAGAGCUUUUUGUGGAAUCUAUUGAGUUGGAUGGGAAAAGGGACAAGCAGAAAGAGCAGGUGGUGCAAACUGGAAUUUGAGGCUCAGCUGCCCCACCCCCGGGGUCUCCUGCAAUGAACUCGGAUAACCAAUGUGCUGUCAAGCCCUUGCCUGUUUGUCCUGAACCCCAUUCAAGAAAACACAGACUUAAAGUACUUAGUUUACAGUAACUUUUGAUGAUUGUUGAAAGUUGUAAAUCAGAAGGUAGGGCUGUGAUGGUGGUUGUCACUUGAGUCAUUUAGUUACUGUUGUCCUGUUCAUAAGCCUGUGUUCACCACCACCAUCAGACUCACCAUUUAUAAGUAGAAGAGCACUAGGGUUGAUCUGCCACCUCAUCUUUCAUGAAGUCUAUUCCCCAGCCUCCUUUUUAAGAAAAGAUACUGCUACCAAAGGCAUAGGGGAGGCCUGCUGUGCUGGCAAUUAGCAUGAGCCUGCAGAAGUCAUCCUUGAAUCUGUUGUGUCUUAAUUUUAUUUGGACAGUUUUUUUUUCCAGCCUCAUCAACACUUGGUCUUCCUGGUGUCUUAAUUCCCUCAGACAAGUUUAUGCACUUUUUUAAGGAAAUAUUUUUCAGGACACUAGUAAGAAGCUCAGUUCACAGUUUGGAUAUUUCUUCCCACAUUACAGAAUUAUGGAAAGGAACUCAAAAUCAGCCUAGGAAAGUGAGUCCUGCUUGACCCAUGUGACUGUGUACCUGACCUUCUGGGAUCUUUUCAGCUAUUAAAACAUUUUACUGUUCCCACAUACCCAGCUUUGCAAGUUUUGUAGAUUGACCUCUUAGGGUGUGUUUCUUUGUCUUUCCUGCCUUUAACUUGCUGGGGUCUUUUGUUGCUACCCCUAAGGAACUAAACUGGGUGCCAGGAGCUACCUUCGUGUAUAGAGAUGUAGAUGGCAGUGUGGGGUACAGGAGAGCCAUCCAGGCCAUUCUCCCAGGGAUGAGGAAUUGGAGAGCCCUGAAGAUAAUAGUGGCUUCUUUCUGAUUGCUACUGUGCUGUGUGAUAGGCCUAAUAGGGAAAAGAUAUGUAACUUGAAACAAAGUUGGUAUAAAUUCAGUAUGUGGCUGUGGGACAGAGGUUGGAAGGAAAGGACUAGGGUAUGGAAAGCUGAAGAAAUUCUCCUUAUGAGCUCUCGUUGACUUUUUGAACAGUGAUAAGCUAAUGCCAGAUUUAAAAUACACAUUUUUUCCUAUUUGAGUCUUUAGGAUUAUAUCAUUUGAAAAAAUUGCCUUCCUUGUUAGGUCACAUGUCAUAGGAGAGUAGCUUAGAGAACUUGCAUUACCAGACAGACACAUUAAUUCCCAAAGCCUCUAUGUUGAGAGAAUGAAACUGUUAACUCUUUUUCAGAGAGGACUAUGAAUAAAGAAACUUCUUUAUUCAAGCUUCAGCUUUCAGCUGGGUUGUUUCCUCUAAAAGGGAAAGGGCAUUGCAAGUGCAUAGAGGAAAUCUCUCCCUUCUGGGACUGCUUUUCCUCCUUCAUCCUCGUGAGCCUGUCCAAGCUCAGAAUUCCGAAGGCUGUUAGAAAUGCGUUGGGAUUGCAGAGAGAAAGGAGCUUGUCUUUCCUUCUGCUGUGCUGGUCUGUUUUGGAUGUCAGUCUUCAGGACUAUGAAAACUUCCUGCCAGUUUAGCAUGGACACUGAGGGCUGGCAUUUCUAGUCUUCUUCAGACACUGAACAUACUGACUCCAGGUAUAGGAAGCAGCUAGCAAAUUGAUUCUUUUUUAAAUGCAUAGGACUCUGCUUCCGGCGGUUCCUCUUGUAGUCCAACUCUUUUUGCCAUCUAUUUAUGUUGGGAGGUAGGGGCACAAUUGUCACUCACAACACAGGCUAGUUAGAGUUUGCUACCUUCUUAGCAGAAAAUGCAUGUGUGUCUUGUUGGACCUUCACUGGGGAAAGGCUGGGAGCCUCUGGCUGUCAGUGACUUUUCUCACAGAAGAAGAACCAGCAAGCCAGACUGGACACCUUUACCCUUUAAUGGUAAGACUUGUAUUUAUAAGGGGUAAUUUUGAUGUUGAAUUUAAGCCACUACUUUGUUUAAACUUUUUUAAAUUGGCAACUAGAAGUUUGAGAAUUUGUAUAGAAAUGGAACAUGUAUUUCUAACAGUUGCCAAUCUGGCUGGUCCCAAUGUUAGUUUAUUAGUGAUUGAUCUGUAAUUAUUGGGAUUAUUUAUUCAACUCUAAAAUUCCAAGAUGAAAAUAAUUUAUCUCUUUCUUUUCAAGGGAAAAAACCCAAAUGAAUGCAUUUUCAGUUUCUCCAGGCCUUUGAACUGCAGCAGAAAAUUCAAGGAUACAGCCUAGGCCUGGGCAAAUGCAGCCCUGGGUCUUUGGGCCAGUUUCUGACAAUAAUAGUUGAGUUUUGGGAAUCACAUAAGGGUGAAACCAGAAACGAUCCUAAGGAAAGGCUUGACCUUUGUUAACACCUUUAGUUUCCAAAGUCACAGCAGCUGGGGUCCCUCUUUUUUUUUUUUUUUUCUUUUUUUUUGAGACAUAGUCUCACUCUGUCACCCAGGCUGGAGUGCAGUGGUAUGACCAUAGCUCACUGCAGCAUCAAAUUCCUAGGCUCAAGCAAUCCUCCCAUCUUAGCCUCCCGAGUAGCUGGGACAACAGGUACGCACCACCACGGCCAGCUAAUUAUUUUUAUUAUUUUUAUUUUUUGUAGAGACUGGAUCUUGCUCUAUUUCCCAAGCUACUCUUGAAUUGUUGUGCUCAAGUGAUUCUCCCAUCUCAGCCUCCCAAAGUGCUGGGAUUAUAGGCUGGGUGUGGUGAGCCACCCCAGCCUGGGGUCUCUUUAAUUAAGGUUAUAAUGCUAACCAUGGCUUAAAAUACUAAGCAACAUUUUCCAAAUUGUUUAUUACUAUUGCUUUGAUUUUGGAGAAGCUGGGAAGUAAGGAGGUGAGGUGAAUACUCUGAUAAUUAACACGUGUUAGAGAGGAAAGUUGUGUGAAGAGGCUGCCAAAGUAAACAGCACGAAUGAAUCUUCUUGUACUAGGGCUGCUGCAAACCCCAGGUAGACAAAUGACAGCCCAGGCUCCUGAACCAUCAGGAACCCAGGAAUCUACCCAACUGUGAGGAGGGGGCAGGCCUUCGUCAAUAAGGGUCCCACCAUCACGGGCUAAUAAUCUUUCUCAGUUUAGGUGAUAUUGAGGUAUUGAAACUGUUAGAAAUCUGACAGAUUUGACCAAGAUUUGGAGACGUCCACAUAAUUGGGAAGGACUGAGUGUCCCUAGCCACUCUCCUCUGGGAUAACGCGGACGUCAUUAGUUUGCGAAGUGGGUGGGGAGAACAGGAGGAUUGACUCUAAUUUGGUGUGUAGUGGGGGCCUUGAUGUCCUUCUGCCUCUGUCCACAUUUCCCCAUGUGACUCAUUGCACCCUGCAUUGCUCACAGGGAUCAUUAGUUCUCCCGGUAGACAGAGCACCUCUGCAGCCUCUGCUCUGCUGCCUUGUGAAUUUCCUACACAGACUUGGUUAGUUACAAUUUGGAAACAGUUUUUUUGGGUUUUUUUCCUUUGUUUUAAUCUUCUCACAAUGAAGCUGCUAUUGGUGACAGGGACAGGGGAGCAGGAAGCCAACCCAGGGAAACAUGCGAGUUUCCUGCACACCACUUAGUCACCUGCCCUCACUGGCCAACCCCCUACUGCUGUUCCCAGUCAGUCUGGUUUUUAGAGGCAUCGUGGCAAUAGAAUAGCUGGAUACACUAAUCUCUACAAGGUGUCAGGCAGGAGAUUCACCUUCCCCAGUCCCAGGGGACAGGAGAGAAAUCUGUAAAGGGACAGAUGCACCAUCUUUAUUUCAAAAGAAAAAGCUCCCUCAGAUUGUGUUACUAGGAGUCUCUUUUGUGACAUUUACUGAGCUUUCUCCCCAAUCUUACCUUCCUAUUGGCUACUUUUUAAAUAAAAAUAAACAUUUUAGGCUAAUAUGACAAAAAUGAGAUAAAAUCUUAAAAACAUUGUACUAGUGUACAGUUACUAAAAUGUGCUUACUACAAAACAGUAAAAUAUUUCACUCUGUAAAUCAUCACUAAGUAGUUAUUCUGUCCUGUUGAUUAUGAGCCUCCAAAAAUGUUUAAUGCUUGAAGGAUGGUUUGGGAGGCAGGGAAUCCUUUUCUUAAAACAACUUUAAUGAGGCAUAUGUUACAUAUCAUAAAACACCCAUUUCAAGUGUACAUUUCAGUGAUUUUAGUAACUUCCCUCAGUGGUGUAGCUGUAACUAUUACUCAGUUUUAGAACAUUUUUAUCCCUCCCAAUAAGAUCCUUCAUGCUCUUUUACAGUUAAUCCUGUUCUUACCCCCGGCAACCACUAAUCUACUUUCUCUAUAAAUUUGCCCUUUCUGGACAGUUCAAAUCAAUGGAAUCAUACAAUAUGUGGUCCCUUGGGUCUGGCUUUUUUACUUAGCUAAUGUUUUUGAGGUUUGUCCAUGACAGAUAACGUCUUGGUAGUUUGUUCCUUUUAUUGCUGAGUAGAAUUCUGUUGAUGGAUGUACCACAUUUUGUCAGCAGAGAGCCUUUUAAACUUGGAUUCCAACUUCCUGUUGUCUAAACGGAACCCUCCGAACGUAGGACUUAUAGGGGAAGCUGCUGUGCAUGUCAAAAAAACUACUAAUCAGAAUGAGCUUUGUCAUCCAGAGCCAGAACUGCUGCAGAAAUUUUUAUAAUUUUGCAACUUCUUUUUUUACAAGGAACUUUUGUGCUACUACACAUCAGGACUUUUGAAGCAUCCAAUAAAUCCAUUUAAUAAGUAUGAGCAUGUGUCUGAGUGGACAAGAAAGUGAAACCAUCCAUGCUACAUUGGAUAAUUUUUCCUCCCCCAGACUGGACAGGGAAUCUCAGCUUUCAAAACAGAGUAACCUGGCUCCACUUACAAAGCUGCACAGGCAUUAAAGAUCGUGCUGCCUUUGUUAGGCAGAUUUGGAGGGGAGGCCCAACAGCAAAGAUGGAGAGGAAAAAGGGAGUGGAGCUUGUGGAACAGGAAGCCCCCCAGGGUCUGUGCAGGGCUGCUCAGCUCUUGAGGAUGUUGUGGAUGGUGAAGUGGUGAUGGUGUCCCGGAGCAGCCCAGCACCUCCACUGGGCCCAGAAGGUCUUGACUUCGGACACUUACCCCUGUUUCACAAGUGUUUAUAAAGCUGUUUUUGCUUUUUUUCCCCUAAUCAUUACUUGGUAGUUAUUAAUCCUUCUUUGGGGGAGGGACAGGGCUUUAAAACUGAAGAAAAUAAUUUUCAUAAAAAUAUCAAAAAUGGAAAAAAGUUACUUUGUAAAAAAUUUGCUAUACAAACCAAAUGGCAGCUGUUGAGAAUCUCAAUAAAAUGUUAAAUGCA